AGUUGGGCUUGGAGGCGGCAGCGGCUGCCAGGCUACGGAGGAAGACCCCCUUCCCAACUGCGGGGCUUGCGCUCCGGGACAAGGUGGCAGGCGCUGGAGGCUGCCGCAGCCUGCGUGGGUGGAGGGGAGCUCAGCUCGGUUGUGGGAGCAGGCGACCGGCACUGGCUGGAUGGACCUGGAAGCCUCGCUGCUGCCCACUGGUCCCAACGCCAGCAACACCUCUGAUGGCCCCGAUAACCUCACUUCGGCAGGAUCACCUCCUCGCACGGGGAGCAUCUCCUACAUCAACAUCAUCAUGCCUUCGGUGUUCGGCACCAUCUGCCUCCUGGGCAUCAUCGGGAACUCCACGGUCAUCUUCGCGGUCGUGAAGAAGUCCAAGCUGCACUGGUGCAACAACGUCCCCGACAUCUUCAUCAUCAACCUCUCGGUAGUAGAUCUCCUCUUUCUCCUGGGCAUGCCCUUCAUGAUCCACCAGCUCAUGGGCAAUGGGGUGUGGCACUUUGGGGAGACCAUGUGCACCCUCAUCACGGCCAUGGAUGCCAAUAGUCAGUUCACCAGCACCUACAUCCUGACCGCCAUGGCCAUUGACCGCUACCUGGCCACUGUCCACCCCAUCUCUUCCACGAAGUUCCGGAAGCCCUCUGUGGCCACCCUGGUGAUCUGCCUCCUGUGGGCCCUCUCCUUCAUCAGCAUCACCCCUGUGUGGCUGUAUGCCAGACUCAUCCCCUUCCCAGGAGGUGCAGUGGGCUGCGGCAUACGCCUGCCCAACCCAGACACUGACCUCUACUGGUUCACCCUGUACCAGUUUUUCCUGGCCUUUGCCCUGCCUUUUGUGGUCAUCACAGCCGCAUACGUGAGGAUCCUGCAGCGCAUGACGUCCUCAGUGGCCCCCGCCUCCCAGCGCAGCAUCCGGCUGCGGACAAAGAGGGUGACCCGCACAGCCAUCGCCAUCUGUCUGGUCUUCUUUGUGUGCUGGGCACCCUACUAUGUGCUACAGCUGACCCAGUUGUCCAUCAGCCGCCCGACCCUCACCUUUGUCUACUUAUACAAUGCGGCCAUCAGCUUGGGCUAUGCCAACAGCUGCCUCAACCCCUUUGUGUACAUCGUGCUCUGUGAGACGUUCCGCAAACGCUUGGUCCUGUCGGUGAAGCCUGCAGCCCAGGGGCAGCUUCGCGCUGUCAGCAACGCUCAGACGGCUGACGAGGAGAGGACAGAAAGCAAAGGCACCUGAUACUUCCCCUGCCACCCUGCACACCUCCAAGUCAGGGCACCACAACACGCCACCGGGAGAGAUGCUGAGAAAAACCCAAGACCGCUCGGGAAAUGCAGGAAGGCCGGGUUGUGAGGGGUUGUUGCAAUGAAAUAAAUACAUUCCAUGGGGCUCACACGUUGCUGGGGAGGCCUGGAGUCAGGUUUGGGGUUUUCAGAUAUCAGAAAUCCCCUUGGGGGAGCAGGAUGAGACCUUUGGAUAGAACAGAAGCUGAGCAAGAGAACAUGUUGGUUUGGAUAACCGGUUGCACUAUAUCUGUGAGCUCUCAAAUGUCUUCUUCCCAAGGCAAGAGGUGGAAGGGUACUGACUGGGUUUGUUUAAAGUCAGGCAGGGCUGGAGUGAGCAGCCAGGGCCAUGUUGCACAAGGCCUGAGAGACGGGAAAGGGCCCGAUCGCUCUUUCCCGCCUCUCACUGGUGCGAUGGAAGGUGGCCUUUCUCCCAAGCUGGUGGAUAAUGAAAAAUAAAGCAUCCCAUCUCUCGGCGUUCCAGCAUCCUGUCAAUUUCCCUUUUGCUCUAGAGGAUGCAUGUUUAUUUGAGGGGAUGUGGCACUGAGCCCACAGGAGUAAAAGCCCAGUUUGCUAGGAGGUCUGCUUACUGAAAACAAGGAGACCUGGGGUGGGUGUGGUUGGGGGUCUUAAAACUAAUAAAAGCUGGGGUCGGGGGGCUUUUGCAGCUCUGGUGACAUUCUCUCCACGGGGCACAUUUGCUCAGUCACUAAUCCAGCUUGAGUGUCCGUGUGUUCUGCAUGUGCAGGGGUCAUUCUAGUGCCCGGUGUGUUGGCAUCAUCUUUUUGCUCUAGCCCUUCCUCUCCAAAAUAAAAUCAAAUAAAGGAAAAUCUCCACCCA